UGGUAUAAUGAAGAUUUUCUGGUAAAAAAUUAUGGUGAUGGUUGUACAACAUUGUGAAUAGAAUUAGUAUCAUUUAAUUCUACACUUAAAAUUGCUAAUUCAGUACAUUUAUCUUAUGUAUUAUACCAUAUCUAAAGAGAUCUUUGGGAAACAAACACUCGCCCUGAUCAGAUAGUCCUCAUACUCAUGUACACACCCUUCCUGACCUUCUGUAAAAAGGGAUACAAAGAUUUAGGGACAUGAGACAGUUCAGGCAACUGCAGAUCCACAAAAUAUAUGUAUUUGCAAAGAGAAUGAGAGUUAAGCUGGGGGCACAGACCCCAGACACGGAGAGGGUCCCCCUGAAACCUUCACCAAGGACAGCAGAACCCAGAGCCUCCCACCUCCUUCCAUCAAAGUCCUCUCUUCCCAGGACACACAGGACACCUCCCUCCACACCUAGGAGCUGGGGAUCCUCCCGAGACCUCCAGGCCUGGGUCUCUGUCCCUGGGUCAGAGGCCAGGCUGGUGACACUGAAGAUAGCGGGUGGGUCCUUCCCAGCCAUCACCCAGUGAGCCCCUUUCUAGCCCCCAGAGCCACCUCUGUCACUUUCCUGCUGGGCAUCAUUCUGCCUUCCUGGAGCACUGGAGAGCAUGAGGAGACCCAGGGCCCAGCUGGUUUUGUGUGUCACAAAGGGAAAUAAUCUACCGGCUGUGACAGAACCAAGGCCAGAACACAGCAGAGCCUCACUUUUAACUUUCUGGAACGCACCCACCACUGCCUGGCUCUUUAUUGCAUCAGCGCCCUUUGAAGUUGCUGAAGGGGAGAAUGUUCAUCUCUCUGUGGUUUAUCUGCCCGAGAAUCUUUACAGCUAUGGCUGGUACAAAGGGAAAACGGUGGAGCCCAACCAGCUAAUCGCAGCAUAUGUAAUAGACACUCACGUUAGGACUCCAGGGCCUGCAUACAGCGGUCGAGAGACAAUAUCACCCAGUGGAGAUCUGCAUUUCCAGAACGUCACCCUAGAGGACACGGGAUACUACAACCUACAAGUCACAUACAGAAAUUCUCAGAUUGAACAGGCAUCUCACCAUCUCCGUGUAUACGAGUCAGUGGCUCAGCCCUCCAUCCAAGCCAGCAGCACCACAGUCACAGAGAAGGGCUCCGUGGUCCUGACCUGCCACACAAAUAACACUGGAACCUCUUUCCAGUGGAUUUUCAACAACCAGCGUCUGCAGGUCACGAAGAGGAUGAAGCUGUCCUGGUUUAACCAUGUGCUCACCAUAGACCCCAUCAGGCAGGAGGACGCUGGGGAGUAUCAGUGUGAGGUCUCCAACCCAGUCAGCUCCAACAGGAGCGACCCCCUCAAGCUGACUGUAAAAUCAGAUGACAACACUCUAGGCAUCCUGAUCGGGGUCCUGGUUGGGAGUCUUCUGGUGGCUGCACUUGUGUGUUUCCUGCUCCUCCGAAAAACUGGCAGGGCCAGCGAUCAGAGUGACUUCAGGGAGCAGCAGCCCCCAGCCUCCACCCCCGGCCAUGGACCCUCUGACAGCUCCAUCUCCUAGAUUCCCCUACCCAGCACCAGGGCAGCUGCUCUCAUCUAUGAGGAAUUGCUACACUCUGACACAAACAUUUACUGCUGGAUCGACCACAAAGCAGAUGUGGCUUCUUAGGUUCCUCUGGGAGCUGCUCCUGUGGGUUGAUGGAGCGUCCCUGAAGCCCCCAGCCCUGGGGAUGGGGAAGGACAUGGAGCCUGAGCCAGAGAACCAGCUCUGAGUCCUGAGGAGACACAGGCCUGGGGACAGGAAGGGAUGGGGGUCCCUGCUGAAUAUAUAGAGACCUCAACAGACUGCCCCGGGCUCUGGGUGGGCCAAGGCGAAGGCUUCCCAUCACCACAGGAAGUGGGGGCUUGCAGGGAAAGUGAAUGGGCCUAUGGCCCACCCGGGGUCACCUGGAAAGGAUCUGAAUAAAGGGGAAACUUCCUCUCA